GGGAAGCGGCGCGCGCUGCGCGGGAGGUGACGGUGCCUCUGACUGUCCGGGUCCCUCCAGCAUUUUGCAGCUUUCUCCUGUCUUGAAGAAGUAGAACGGUGCCCGAGAAACGUUUUUCCCCUUCGAGACUCAGGAGGAUGAAAGUCAUCACUUGUGAAAUAGCCUGGCACAACAAGGAGCCCGUGUACAGCCUGGACUUCCAGCAUGGGACGGCUGGGAGGAUCCACAGACUGGCGUCUGCCGGCGUGGACACCAAUGUCAGGAUCUGGAAGGUAGAAAAGGGACCAGAUGGAAAAGCCAUCGUGGAAUUUUUGUCCAAUCUUGCUCGUCAUACCAAAGCCGUCAAUGUUGUGCGUUUUUCUCCAACUGGGGAAAUUUUAGCAUCGGGAGGAGAUGAUGCUGUCAUCCUAUUGUGGAAGGUGAAUGAUAACAAGGAGCCGGAGCAGAUCGCUUUUCAGGAUGAGGACGAGGCCCAGCUGAACAAGGAGAACUGGACGGUUGUGAAGACUCUGCGGGGCCACUUAGAAGAUGUGUAUGAUAUUUGCUGGGCAACUGAUGGGAAUUUAAUGGCUUCUGCCUCUGUGGAUAACACAGCCAUCAUAUGGGAUGUCAGCAAAGGACAAAAGAUAUCAAUUUUUAAUGAACAUAAAAGUUAUGUCCAAGGAGUAACCUGGGACCCUUUGGGUCAAUAUGUUGCUACUCUGAGCUGUGACAGGGUGCUGCGAGUAUACAGUAUACAGAAGAAGCGUGUGGCUUUCAAUGUUUCGAAGAUGCUGUCUGGAAUAGGGGCUGAAGGAGAGGCAAGAAGCUACCGGAUGUUUCACGACGACAGCAUGAAGUCUUUCUUCCGUAGACUGAGUUUCACUCCCGACGGAUCUUUGCUUCUCACGCCAGCUGGAUGUGUGGAAUCUGGUGAAAAUGUAAUGAAUACCACUUAUGUUUUCUCCAGGAAGAAUCUUAAAAGGCCCAUCGCUCAUCUUCCAUGUCCUGGAAAAGCCACUCUUGCUGUUCGCUGCUGUCCGGUCUACUUUGAACUGAGGCCAGUGGUGGAAACAGGUGUGGAGCUGAUGAGUCUGCCCUACCGCCUGGUGUUUGCUGUGGCCUCGGAGGAUUCCGUGCUUCUGUAUGACACCCAGCAGUCCUUCCCUUUUGGUUACGUGUCUAAUAUACAUUACCACACCCUCAGUGACAUUUCAUGGUCCAGCGAUGGUGCCUUCCUGGCCAUUUCUUCCACGGACGGUUACUGCUCAUUUGUGACAUUUGAGAAAGAUGAACUUGGAAUUCCUUUGAAAGAGAAGCCAGUUUUGAACAUGAGAACUCCUGAUACAGCAAAGAAAACCAAGAGUCAGACACAUCGAGGGUCUUCGCCAGGACCCAGACCGGUAGAGGGAACCCCUGCCAGCAGAACCCAAGACCCCAGCAGCCCCGGCACGACUCCCCCUCAGGCCAGACAGGCCCCAGCCCCAACAGUCAUCAGGGACCCUCCCUCCAUCACUCCUGCUGUCAAAAGCCCCUUGCCGGGGCCUUCGGAGGAGAAGACCCUGCAGCCCAGUAGUCAAAACACAAAAGCCCACCCAUCCCGGAGGGUCACUCUGAACACACUGCAAGCCUGGAGCAAGACAACACCCCGGAGAAUAAACUUAACACCCUUAAAGACGGACACUCCACCAAGUUCUGUACCAACCAGUGUGAUUUCCACCCCUUCUACAGAAGAAAUUCAGUCAGAGACGCCUGGAGACGCUCAGGGCAGUCCCCCAGAGCUAAAGCGGCCCAGACUCGAUGAAAACAAAGGAGGCACGGAAAGUCUGGACCCUUGAUGGGACCUCGGCUUCUGCUCGAAGCCUACCAGGCUCCCGGUGUGUGCAGGGAGACGGUAAAGCUGGAGGUGCCUGAGACCAGGGCUUCCAUGGAGCGGGACACACUGUAAAUGGAUUUCUAUAACAGAAGUGACAUGUGUACUGAUUUUUCUCCAGAAAUAUGGAUGCUGUUGUAUUCAGUAUCCAUUUUUAACUUGGGACAUGAACGUUUUAACGUAGUAAAUCCUCUUUUUGAUGAGUUUCUGAAACUGGAGCGGUUCAACGUUAUCCAGUGUGAAAAUCAGUGAGUCCUCCCUGGCAUCCUCGUGAAAGUGCACACACUUCAUGGAGGGACUCCUUUUCAAUAAGAAUUAGGAAGAUGAGAAAGUAAUUUGAGAUUUUACUCUGUCGAAUUUUAGAGUAUUUGAAGUGAUUGUUAGAUUUCACUUCUAAGGAGUUGAUUGAUUAAACUUUGGAAGGUAGUUGUGUUUGUUUUCUGAUUUUAAAGGUGACGAUGCUUAUUCUUUUAGUAACUAAGUGAAGUGAAAAAGAUGGGUAUCACCCAUCAUCUUCCCACCAGAAGUAACCCUCGUUAAUGUUGUAGUAUAUUUCCUUAGCAUUUUUGUGGAUCUAUUUAUUCUAAAAAGAGAAUUGAGAUUUUAUUUCAUAUGCAAUUUGGUAUCUAAAUAGGUUAGUUUUUUAGAUUGGUUUUUCAAAGCAAAAAAAGUAUCUUUUUUGUUUUUUGAGACAGGGUCUUGCUCUGUUGCCCAGGCUGGAGUGCAGUGGCGCUAUCUCAGCUCACUGCAGCCUCGACCUCCUGGGCUCGAGCGAUCCUUCCACCUCAGCUUCCCGAGUAGCUGGGACUACAGGCAUGUGCCACCAUGCCAUGCUAAUUUCACACACACAUGCACCCACACACACACAUAUAUAUGAUACAUAUAUAUAUAUAUACACACACACACAAGUAUGUGUGUAUAUAUAUAUUUUUUUUCUUUUUUUUUUGAGAUGGAGUCUCACUCUGUCGCCCAGGCUGGAGUACAGUGGCACAAUCUCGGCUCACUAUAACCUCCGCCUCCUGGGUUCAAACGAUUCUCCUGCCUCUGCCUCUUGAGUAGCUAGGAUUACAGGUGUGUGCCACCACAUCCGGCUAAUUUUUAUAUUUUUAGUAGAGAUGGGGUUUUGCCAUGUUGGCCAAGCUGGUCUCUAACUCCUGACCUCAGAUGAUCUGCCUGCCUCGGCCUCCCAAAGUGUUGGGAUUACAGGUGUGAGCUACUGCACCUGGCCUAAUUAUUAUAUUUUUAGGGGAGACGGGGUUUUUCCAUGUUGCCCAGGCUGGUCUCGAACUCCUGGGGCUCAAGUAAUCCUCCCUCCCCAGCCUCCCAAAGUGUUGGGAUUACAGGCGUGAGACACCAUGCCUGGUCAAAUGGUAUCUGUUUUGACGGGUGGUUCUCAACUGUAGCUGCAUACUGAAAUCACCUAAGAGCUGACAUACCAGUGCCUGGGUUCCCGCUUCGGAGGAUUUGGCCUAAUCGGUCUGGGGUAUGUUCUGAAUAUUAGGAUUUCUUAAAGCUCCUGGAGUAAUUCUGAUGCGCAGCCAAGAUUGAGAAAUCUAAGGGAAAAAACUUUCCCUGGAUACGGUCUGUUCUGGUUAAAUGCAUUUCCACUGAAAGCAUUUUUUUUUUUUUCCGAGACAGAGUCUCGCUCUGUCACCCAGGCUGGAGUGCAGUGGCGCAAUCUCCACUCACUGCAACCUCACCUCCUAGGUUCAAGGGAUUCUCCUGCCUCAGCCUCUCCAGUAGCUGGGAUUACAGGCACCCGCCACCACGCCCGGCUAAUUUUUGUAUUUUUAGUAGAGAUGGUGUUUCACCAUGUUGGUCAGGCUGGUCUCCAACGCCUGACCUCGUGAUCUGCCCACCUCAGCCUCCCAAAGUGCUGGGAUUACAGGCGUGAGCCACCGCGCCCAGCCGAAAGCAUUUUCUUGAUUAUCUCUGCCCCGUCACUGAUUGACAUCCUCCUUUGCUGGGGCCGCGGACUGAAGGACAGUAUGCAGGAGGUGCCAUCAGCUCUUCUGAAAAGAGACAGCUUUCAGUGUCAUGUGGCUGGCGUGAGGUGCGGUUUGCAGUUGUUGAUCCUGUGCAGACAGAUGAAUGACCAUGGGUCCCCUGUCCUUAUUGAGCAGCCUGCUUCCUGGCCAUACCUGGGGAGGAACAGUAUUAGGUUUUUCUGGGUGUGGUGGCUCACACCUGUAAUCCCAGCACUUUGGGAGGCCAAGGUGGGUGGAUCACUUGAGGUUGGGAGUUUGAGACCAGCCUGGCCAACAUGGUGGAACCCCAUCUCUACUAAAAAUACAAAAACUAGCCAGGCGCGGUGGCACACACUUGUAAUCCCAGCUACUCGGGAGGCUGAGGCACAAGAAUCGCUUGAACCCGGGAGGCGGAGUUUGUAGUGAGCUGAGAUGGUGCCACUGUACUCCAGCCUGGGCGACAGAGCGAGACUCUGUCUCAAAAAAAAAAAAAAAGAGAAAAAGAAGAACAGUAUUAGGUUUUACAAAUCUGUUUCUUGUGCAUUGAUUGUGGGAGUUGGGGUGGGGGACCCCUGAUGGCCUGCCUGUUCUCAGCCAUCAUCCUUAAAUAUAAAUCAAAAUUGGCAAUAAAAGACCAAGUGAAGUCA